AGAAAUCACUAAACCUUGGCCAUGGUCACUUCCUCUUUUCCAAUCUCUGUGGCAGUUUUUGCCCUAAUAACCCUGCAGGUUGGUACUCAGGACAGUUUUAUAGCUGCAGUGUAUGAACAUGCUGUCAUUUUGCCAAAUAAAACAGAAACACCAGUUUCUCAGGAGGAUGCCUUGAAUCUCAUGAACGAGAAUAUAGACAUUCUGGAGACAGCGAUCAAGCAGGCAGCUGAGCAGGGUGCUCGAAUCAUUGUGACUCCAGAAGAUGCACUUUAUGGAUGGAAAUUUACCAGGGAAACUGUUUUCCCUUAUCUGGAGGAUAUCCCAGACCCUCAGGUGAACUGGAUUCCGUGUCAAGACCCCCACAGAUUUGGUCACACACCAGUACAAGCAAGACUCAGCUGCCUGGCCAAGGACAACUCUAUCUAUGUCUUGGCAAAUUUGGGGGACAAAAAGCCAUGUAAUUCCCGUGACUCCACAUGUCCUCCUAAUGGCUACUUUCAAUACAAUACCAAUGUGGUGUAUAAUACAGAAGGAAAACUCGUGGCACGUUACCAUAAGUACCACCUGUACUCUGAGCCUCAGUUUAAUGUCCCUGAAAAGCCGGAGUUGGUGACUUUCAACACCGCAUUUGGAAGGUUUGGCAUUUUCACGUGCUUUGAUAUAUUCUUCUAUGAUCCUGGUGUUACCCUGGUGAAAGAUUUCCAUGUGGACACCAUACUGUUUCCCACAGCUUGGAUGAACGUUUUGCCCCUUUUGACAGCUAUUGAAUUCCAUUCAGCUUGGGCAAUGGGAAUGGGAGUUAAUCUUCUUGUGGCCAACACACAUCAUGUCAGCCUAAAUAUGACAGGAAGUGGUAUUUAUGCACCAAAUGGUCCCAAAGUGUAUCAUUAUGACAUGAAGACAGAGUUGGGAAAACUUCUCCUUUCAGAGGUGGAUUCACAUCCCCUAUCCUCGCUUGCCUACCCAACAGCUGUUAAUUGGAAUGCCUACGCCACCACCAUCAAACCAUUUCCAGUACAGAAAAACACUUUCAGGGGAUUUAUUUCCAGGGAUGGGUUCAACUUCACAGAACUUUUUGAAAAUGCAGGAAACCUUACAGUCUGUCAAAAGGAGCUUUGCUGUCAUUUAAGCUACAGAAUGUUACAAAAAGAAGAGAAUGAAGUAUACGUUCUAGGAGCUUUUACAGGAUUACAUGGCCGAAGGAGAAGAGAGUACUGGCAGGUCUGCACACUGCUGAAGUGCAAAACUACUAAUUUGACAACUUGUGGACGGCCAGUAGAAACUGCUUCUACAAGAUUUGAAAUGUUCUCCCUCAGUGGCACAUUUGGAACAGAGUAUGUUUUUCCUGAAGUGCUACUUACCGAAAUUCAUCUGUCACCUGGAAAAUUUGAGAAAUCUAUCUCUUUGAGGAAUUGUCCCAUAGUAGGACUGAACAUUUACCUGAUGAAACUACUUCAUCCAUGGGAGAAGGACAAAAAAAUGCUAGAGUUUUCCAAACUAGGUUAAAGGUCCAAAGCCAGAAAUACCAUUUCACUCUUACUCUGAACCACAUAAGUGUUUGAAGGUGGAUGGUGAUAGUGCAUGAAGAGUUGGAGAACGUAAAUAAUUUAUUCCAUUACUACUUCCUUUCUUUGUUUUAAAAAUUUCAUCCCAAAUGUCUUCAGGCAGUUAAGAAGAGUUAGAGAAUGAUACAAGAGAAUACAUGUUUAAAUGCUUAACUCCAUAGUAUUUGUACAUCUCAACUCUUAAACAUUUUUUUAAAUUAUUUUUAAUUAUUAUUAUUAUUUGAGAUGGCGUCUCGCUGUGUUGCCCAGACUGGAGUGCAGUGGUGCAAUCUCAGCUCACUGCAAACUCUGCCUCUUGGGUUCAAGCGAUUCUCCUGCCUCAGCCUCAUAAGUAGCUGGGACUACAGGUGCAUGCCACCACGCCCAGCUACUUUUUGUAUUUUUGGUGGAGAUGGGGUUUCACCAUAUUGGCCAGGCUGGUCUCGAACUCCUAACAUCUAGUGAUCUGCCACCUCGACCUCCCAAAGUUCUGGAAUUACAGGCAUGAGCCACCAUGCCUGGCCUUGUUUUUAAUUUUUGUGGGUACAUAGUAGGUGUAUAUAUUUAUGGGUUACAGGAGAUAUUUUGAUACAGACAUGCAAUGUGUAAUAAUCACAUUAGGGUAAAUAUGGUAUCAGUAGGUCUCAACUUUUAAUGAUUCUGUGAACUUGUCAUGCUGUAUCCCAUCUCUGGUUCCUUCUUAGAUGGAAGGAAGGAGGGAAGGGGGCAUAGCACCUACCGUUUAAAUUGGGCACCUGUAAUCAUUAUUUGGAUCUUGUCUUACCUGCUCCAGACCAUUUGCAGAAGAAGGAAAUGAGAUAUAGAUUGUAUUACACCAAAAAAGAUAUGAAAGAGCCAUGUGACAGCUGGCAGGGAGGGUCUUUGGAAUUGUAGUCCCUUGGAGGGAGCAUCAUGAUGAGGGUGAGGCAGGUCUUUAUUUUGUAAGUGUAGAUUCUCUGUGGCAUGACUUUCACUGAAGUUCAUCAGGUUCUAAGGAACAGAUACUAAUCAAAUUUGCAAGAUAGAUAAGCGAGAACACCAACUUGUUAUUUUAAAAAAUAGGUUCCCUUAGCUGGGAACAAUGAACUGUAUGUCAAGGAGACUCUUCAUUGGCAAAUCCUCUCAAAAGUACAAAUGAUAGAUCAGUUUGUUUUGUGAGUGCAGAAUUAAAACAAAAGGAGUUGGGCAUUCUUGGAAAAGAUUUCCAAGAACCCACAGAAGCCUGAGGCAAUGUGAUUCUUCUCUUUAGGGCUGGUGAUCUGAAGACCAUGUAGGAUCAAGGUGCCCACUUUCCUCAAAAAGAGCCAAAAAAAAGUCCAAUAACCCAUUCUUGGUUUUUUUAGUGCUUCUUUUCUCUAGAGACCUUGCAGGGCAUGGCCCUUCUGUGAAUAUGUUGUUUCUAGAAACAGCAGUCAUAAUAUUGAAGAUGACAAAUGUUUUACAUCAGUCAUGCUCAUUAUGGCUUCUUGAGUAGCUUCUCAGUUCUGUUGAUGGAUGCACACUCUCUCCAUAGAUAUUUACACGUUAUCUUAGAGGAUCACUAUUGCAGAGAUUUCAACACACUUGUUGUGUAUCCUCAACCCCCACCACCACUUUAGUUUUAUGUUAAAAGGGUGGUGUUACUCACCAUGCCCACAAAUGUGGAAACAUCUUGCUUUAGCACCUUAGGCAACUCUGGUGUAUUGUCAGAAGCACUGGCAGAGUCUGUUCUCUGUAACUAACUAGUUAGAUAACCUUGGGAAAGUCACUUAACCUCUGAAUUUCCUACUCAUAGAAGAGAAUAUUUUCCUCACUGAUUUGGUGAGGAUCAAAUAUGAUAAUGCAUGUGAAGACACUUUGUGAAUGGUGAAGUACAAUCAUUAUCUUCUAGGAUAUUUAGUCAUUUUCUCCUCCCAGUUGUAAAGCAUCUGUUUUCCUAAUUUUCAAUUUCUUCUCCACUCCAACUAAUUUCCCAAUUUUCAAUUUCUUCUCCAUUCCAACUCCAUUUCCACAACUAAUGGGUUCAUUUUCUUUUAUUCUUGUUCUGUUUAUUGACUGUCUAUGCAUGUUUCCUUCUGUUCUUGUUCAAUUGCUUUGUACAUAUUCCUCUCUUAUGAAAACUCCACUGUGGCUUCAGGCUAGAUCUAGUCAUUAAUGCCUUUCACAGUCUGAUCUCCACCUUCCUCUGAUCAUAUUCCUUCUUCUCUUCUUCACUAAUCUUCAGCGCUAGCCAGUGGUGUGAUGUAACUUUAAACAAUUCCUUCUCUGAGGUAGAAAACAAAAAGCCCUGACUUAUGGAAUUUGCCAGUUUUCAUUGUGUCAAUAUUCCCGCCAUGAUCCCACCAGCUUCAAGAAUGGAUCUGUUGGCAGAGUUUGAUAGCUCACGCCUGUAAUCCCAGCACUUUGGGAGGCUGAGUUGGGAGGACCAUUUGAGGCCAGGAGUUCGAGA